AGACCUGGGCAGGCAGGCGCGGGUGAGCAUCCUCUGAGAGCUUGGGUCUUGCGUAUGUGGAAGGCCGCCAGGGAGACCAGUGCCGCCCACCAUGCGAUUUCGACGCUUGACCCCUGGUUACUUCCGGGUGUUACAGAUGCAGGUAGCUGGUGAGCUGAAGGCAGAGCCCCGGAGUCUGCUGGCAGGAGUUGUGGCUACAGUGCUAGCUGUCCUCGGCCUGGGUGGCUCCUGCUAUGCCGUCUGGAAGAUGGUGGGGCAGCGGCGGGUGCCACGGGCCCCGUAACGAAGAAGAGAGACUCUCACUUGGAUGCUGGGGGGCUCGACGCUCAGCUGCUUCAGCCUGGGAGAAAGAAAAACAGGAGUUGGGAGCUGACCAGGUGAGAGCCCUAUCUGCUGAGCACCCAUCCAUCAAUCCUCUCCUUACUCCUUCAUACCUUUUCUUGUGGUCUUUGGAUCGGAAGUGGGUCUUCAGGUUGGUGGAAUCGAUGAAGUACCUCCUGUAGGAAUGGAAGUGAGAAGGAGAGUGAGGAGGUGAUAGUCUCCCAAGUGCACCUAUCUCCCUAGCCCUAGCUUGUCCCUGACGCCAGGAUCCGGGUCUGAGAAACGGGAGGCGGGCGGACCCACGGGUCCCAAGAGAGAAGACUCUGCGCUGCCUGGGGCUUCAACUUCACAUCUCCCGGCCGGUACCGCGGACCCUCCUCCGCCCCAGGCCGGGCUCGUCCGGGACUCACGCGCAGGCCAGACAGCGGUGCAGACCGCCCCCUGGCAGGUCGGGGUCGAACUCGGCGUUUGGGUCGGGCUGGGGUCGUGCGGAUCCCUGAGGCCGCAGCUCGCGGUGAAUCUCAUCCAAGUCCGGCCGCCGCCGCUUCGCCUUCAUCUGCCGGGCUAGAGAGUGCGCUCGGUGCGCGCCUGUCCGGCGGGAGCGACCCAUGGCCAGAAACAGCCCGGCCGGCCAAGGGGCCAGGAGCAGGGCAGGGAGCACACGUGUGAGCACUUCCGGGCCGAUCAGCUACGUCAGGCCACGCCGGGGGGCUAGGCAGGCUCGGCCGGACCGCCUCUGAUGACGUCACUCUCGGCCAGCGGCUCGAGCGCCGCCAGGCGGCCGUCGACGUCAGUGACCGAGCUCAGGACGGGCUCCCAGAAGUGUGCCCACUGAAGGGCAUGGCCCCGCGGGCCCUCGCUGGGGAGGCGCGGGGUGGUGCGUGCGCCUGGGGGUUUCGGGGCCGUCUUGCUGCCCUGCUCUUCCUGGCCUGGUCCAACCAGUAUCAGUGCCAACCUGUACUCCUGUCAUCCCUUCCUGUUUCCCAGACCUUGGACUCCGCGGUGGGGGUGGGAUGCUUUAUCUCUGGAAAGCACUGAUAAAUGUCUGUGUCAUGAAUAAAUUAGUAAAUGAC